AGUUUCAGCCCACACAAGAAGGGUAGGAGAGAAAAGCCAUGGCCGGUGAGUCUUUUACUGUUCCAAGAACAGGUCCCUGGGAAGAAAGAGUUGUGGAAAGGGCUGGCUCUUCUGGAAGCCAUAAUUAGUAUCUGUGGAAGUUUAGACAAGGUCCUGAAGGAGAAGAGAAAGCUGUUUAUCCAUUCCAUGGGUGAAGGUACAAUAAAUGGCUUACUGGAUGAAUUAUUACAGACAAGGGUGCUGAACCAGGAAGAGAUGGAGAAAGUAAAACGUGAAAAUGCUACAGUUAUGGAUAAGACCCGAGCUUUGAUUGACUCCGUUAUUCCGAAAGGGGCACAGGCAUGCCAAAUUUGCAUCACAUACAUUUGUGAAGAAGACAGUUACCUGGCAGAGACGCUGGGACUCUCAGCAGGUCCGAUACCUGGAAAUUAGCUUAGUACACAAGACUCCCAAUUACUAUUUUCUUCCUUCCCAGCUCUUCAGGCAGUGCAGGACAACCCAGCUAUGCCCACAUGCUCAAGCCCAGAAGGCAGAAUCAAGCUUUGCUUUCUAGAAGACGCUCAAAGGAUAUGGAAACAAAAGUUGCAGAGGUGCCAUGUUCAGAAUACAAUAAUAAAGUGGAGUGAAAGAUA